AGAACAUGGGAGGCACUGAACUUACUACAUCAGAACUCCUGCUGAGGUAUAAGAGGAUACGUCUAAUAACUCAAUUGCUGUAAACCUAUGAUUGUUUUUCUGGUUUUUAAACAUCUCUUCAGCCUCAGAUUGAUUACAAUGUUCUUUCUACUUCAUUUCAUCGUUCUGAUCAAUGUCAAAGAUUUUGCACUGACUCAAGGUAGCAUGAUCACUCCUUCAUGCCAAAAAGGAUAUUUUCCCUGUGGGAAUCUUACCAAGUGCUUACCCCGAGCUUUUCACUGUGAUGGCAAGGAUGACUGUGGGAACGGGGCGGACGAAGAGAACUGUGGUGACACUAGUGGAUGGGCGACCAUAUUUGGCACAGUGCAUGGAAAUGCUAACAGCGUGGCCUUAACACAGGAGUGCUUUCUAAAACAGUAUCCACAAUGCUGUGACUGCAAAGAAACUGAAUUGGAAUGUGUAAAUGGUGACUUAAAGUCUGUGCCGAUGAUUUCUAACAAUGUGACAUUACUGUCUCUUAAGAAAAACAAAAUCCACAGUCUUCCAGAUAAAGUUUUCAUCAAAUACACAAAACUUAAAAAGAUAUUUCUUCAGCAUAAUUGCAUUAGACACAUAUCCAGGAAAGCAUUUUUUGGAUUAUGUAAUCUGCAAAUAUUAUAUCUCAACCACAACUGCAUCACAACCCUCAGACCUGGAAUAUUCAAAGACUUACAUCAGCUAACUUGGCUAAUUCUAGAUGACAAUCCAAUAACCAGAAUUUCACAGCGCUUGUUUACGGGAUUAAAUUCCUUGUUUUUCCUGUCUAUGGUUAAUAACUACUUAGAAGCUCUUCCCAAGCAGAUGUGUGCCCAAAUGCCUCAACUCAACUGGGUGGAUUUGGAAGGCAAUAGAAUAAAGUAUCUCACAAAUUCUACGUUUCUGUCGUGCGAUUCGCUCACAGUGCUGUUUCUGCCUAGAAAUCAAAUUGGUUUUGUUCCAGAGAAGACAUUUUCUUCAUUAAAAAAUUUAGGAGAACUGGAUCUGUCUAGCAAUACGAUAACGGAACUAUCACCUCACCUUUUUAAAGACUUGAAGCUUCUACAAAAGCUGAACCUGUCAUCCAAUCCUCUUAUGUAUCUUCACAAGAACCAGUUUGAAAGUCUUAAACAACUUCAGUCUCUAGACCUGGAAAGGAUAGAGAUUCCAAAUAUAAACACACGAAUGUUUCAACCCAUGAAGAAUCUUUCUCACAUUUAUUUCAAAAACUUUCGAUACUGCUCCUAUGCUCCCCAUGUCCGAAUAUGUAUGCCCUUGACGGACGGCAUUUCUUCAUUUGAGGACCUCUUGGCUAACAAUAUCCUCAGAAUAUUUGUCUGGGUUAUAGCUUUCAUUACCUGCUUUGGAAAUCUUUUUGUCAUUGGCAUGAGAUCUUUCAUUAAAGCUGAAAAUACAACUCACGCUAUGUCCAUCAAAAUCCUUUGUUGUGCUGAUUGCCUGAUGGGUGUUUACUUGUUCUUUGUUGGCAUUUUCGAUAUAAAAUACCGAGGGCAGUAUCAGAAGUAUGCCUUGCUGUGGAUGGAGAGCGUGCAGUGCCGCCUCAUGGGGUUCCUGGCCAUGCUGUCCACCGAAGUCUCUGUUCUGCUACUGACCUACUUGACUUUGGAGAAGUUCCUGGUCAUUGUCUUCCCCUUCAGUAACAUUCGACCUGGAAAACGGCAGACCUCAGUCAUCCUCAUUUGCAUCUGGAUGGCGGGAUUUUUAAUAGCUGUAAUUCCAUUUUGGAAUAAGGAUUAUUUUGGAAACUUUUAUGGGAAAAAUGGAGUAUGUUUCCCACUUUAUUAUGACCAAACAGAAGAUAUUGGAAGCAAAGGGUAUUCUCUUGGAAUUUUCCUAGGUGUGAACUUGCUGGCUUUUCUCAUCAUUGUGUUUUCCUAUAUUACUAUGUUCUGUUCCAUUCAAAAAACCGCCUUGCAGACCACAGAAGUAAGGAAUUGUUUUGGAAGAGAGGUGGCUGUUGCAAAUCGUUUCUUUUUUAUAGUGUUCUCUGAUGCCAUCUGCUGGAUUCCUGUAUUUGUAGUUAAAAUCCUUUCCCUCUUCCGGGUGGAAAUACCAGACACAAUGACUUCCUGGAUAGUGAUUUUUUUCCUUCCAGUUAACAGUGCUUUGAAUCCAAUCCUCUAUACUCUCACAACCAACUUUUUUAAGGACAAGUUGAAACAGCUGCUGCACAAACAUCAGAGGAAAUCAAUUUUCAAAAUUAAAAAAAAAAGUUUAUCUACAUCCAUUGUGUGGAUAGAGGACUCCUCUUCCCUGAAACUUGGGGUUUUGAACAAAAUAACACUUGGAGACAGUAUAAUGAAACCAGUUUCCUAGCAAUCAUUUUGGAUCACUGGACUUUCAGUGGACUACCUAAAACAGGGGACAGCUUUUGGAAGAUGACAUCUGCAAUGCUUUUCAUCUUUACCAACGGCAAGCCUUUCUGCACAGAGAGCACAGCAGAAUGGCUCCUGUCACUGCAUUCCAAUGGCAGCUGUACUAUCUACCAACCAUGCUGAGGACAGCACCAAAGGUUCCUCUCCUCACCCCACAUGCCUGAAAAGCACAUGUGAAUUCGUGUAUAGUGGGCUGAGGUGCAGCUGAUCUCUAGCUAAUCAACACAACCCACCAACAAAUGACCACAGGUUGGCACUGUGUGGUCUUUCACAUCGGGUUGCACUGUCCAUGAAAUAGAAACACUCACAACAUCUGAUUCCAGUGUGGCCAUAAUAACAGAAAUCUAACAACUCUUUCCUUGCCUUUUCAAUAUCAAAUAAAACCAUCAGCAUCCUGCUGGAUUGAUAGCAAAGGAUUUCCAAAAUAUUCAUCUACCCGAAGUCCUCCUCUGUGAAGGCCGGUGGAGUAGCCACUUUGAAAACAGAACUUCCAACCAGGUUACCAUGUCUAACCUAUGACCAGAGAGUCACACUGAUGAAGCCUCAUACCAUUUGCCUUUUGGAUUUUAUUUAAUAUCAGAAGAGAUGAAUUCUUAAGAUAUUUUUCUGAAGGUUGCCCAGGGCACAAACAAAUUGGACACUUUCACUGCUAAAAAGUACACUUUAAUAUUCUUAAAGUAUAAUUUCUUUAGAGCAGUAUCCCUAUUGCUGGCAAGUUCUGCUUUCAUAAAAUAUGCAGAUAAGAAGUGUUAAAUGGGAUUCAAGAAUUAUGGUUUUAUUUGGGACUGUUUGCAUACUCACAAUGGUUUUGUUCUCAUUGUUUUUAACAAAAAAGCAAUGAAGUUUGGGGUGGUUUUUUGAAAACGAAACUGAAAAAAAUUAUAUGUGAAAAUGAGAACUGGGUAAAUAAAAUUAUAUUUUGCAC